AAAAAAAAAAGUACAUUUUACUAAAGAUGUACCUUAACCCAUUUAUGCCGAAUGUACUUUAACCCAUUUGUCUUCAAAUUUAUUCACAUUAAAACCUUAUUAUUGCUCAUACAUUAAUGCAUGUUUCCUUGUUUUCAGGUUUAUGUAUACUGAUUGUCUGUUAUAUAGCCAGGCAAAAUAAAUGUCAGAGUUUGGUAAAGGUUUCCACAAGGAGAAGGGAGGAGUGUUUGCAAAUGAAGGUUAAAUAUGCUAAAAUUACAAAAAUUACAAAUAUCUUAAGUAUUUUCUAAGAAAUGAUGCGUAAAUAUUUGCUACUAAAAGAGUUCUGGCAUUUGAUUCAUGUGGUCUAGAUUCAAAUUCUACCUUUUCAUUCACUGUUUAAAGUUUACAUAACUCUUCUGGAAAAUGGGGAUUCUAAUAGUACUAGUUUAUGAAAGAGUUUUUGUGGAUUUAGUAAAAGAUUAAACUCAUUAACAACUUACAAAGCUCUGCUGUAUUGAAAAUUGAGGAGAAAUAACUUUACAAUAAAUAAAAACUGUUAAAUUUAAAAACAGGGAUAUAGUGUGCAUGUAUCUGCAAUUCUUCUCUCUCUUCUAAGGUUUACUUUGUACAUAACUACCUAGCUGCCCUUCAUGUAACUUAGAACUUCAUCUACUAUCUUUAAAAUCUAGUCCCAUGUUUUAACCAUCUUGGAUGGUUAAAACCUUCAAUGACCUUCACCUAGUUACACAAUUCAGGGACCCAGGAGUCACCAUUAACCCUACACUACUCACAUUCACAUCCAGCUGGCCACUAAGUCAUGUUCAAUCUGUCUUUUAAAAUUCAAUUUAGUAUGUUUCCUUCCUCAUAUUCACCCUUAAAAUUUUCUUUAACUGUAAAUACCAGCAAUUCUAUAUAUUUUUUUCUUAUUUGGCUUAAUUCAUUUAGUUUUUCACUGCAUUUUAUCCCCGCUUUUAUCAGCUACAUUGCUGUGGGUUUAAAAAAUUAUAAUUGGAUCAUAUUAUUCCUCUCUACAAAACUUUUAAUACCAUUCUCUCCAUACACCUUACUCCUAUUUUCUUCAGGAUAAAGUUUGUACUUAUCCUAGAUGACAUUACUUUAUCCAUAGGAUGACCUUACCAAAACCUUUAAGUUCUAGUCUUAACCUACCUGUCUAGCCAUAUCUCUCAUAAGGCCAUAUCUCCUCAUAAAUAUCUAAUGCUUAAUUUUAUGAGAAUUGCUGACAAUUCCUUGAGAUUGUUUUUAUGCUUCCUUAUUUUUUCAAAUCUUAUAUUUUAUCUGGAAUGCCAUUAUAAUAAUGUUUAAUUGAUUUGUAUCAAAACUACUGGGAUUUGUUGAUGGCUUCUUGCCUUAUGUUGUUAGAUAUUUGGCUUUUUUUUUUUGGAGAGAUGGUGUCUCACUAUAUUGCCCAUGCUAGUCUCAAACUCCUUGGCCCAAGUGAUCCUCUCCCUUGGCCUCUCAAAGUGUUGAGAUUAUAGGUGUGAGCCCUUGCGUCCAGCCUUGCCAAUUUUUUUACACAUAUUAUUUAAUGUAAGUUCUAUGGCAAUUUAGUGAGGAAACAGAUACAGAGGAGUUUUAUUUCAUGUCCAAGUUUACAGAAUUAUAAGUGGUAGAGUCAGGCCAAUGCUAUGUUUGCCGCUAAAAACUAUGUUAUCCAAAAGAUGCUGCAAAACUGACCUCAAUCAUAUUCAUGUGUGUGAAACCUUUUGUGACACAUCUACAUAUGAGAUAUUGAUGAUCAUGUUGUCUUUUAUGUUAUCACUAUAUCCACAACUGUUUCUGUUAUCUCAGGUGUCACAUUAUCUCAGGUGUCACACUAAACUUCAACUGUGAACUUUAUGUCUGUUAUUCCCACUUAAUUAUAAACUGAUAAGCAGAAUAACAGUAUUUUAAAAAUCAUAACCUCUUGCCCAGUGUAUAUUUCUCAAUAAAUUACAUUUGAAUGAAUGAAUGAAUAAUACAGAUUCCUUCUUUUUUUUGUAUUCAACUUCACCCAUACAAGAGAGACUAAAAGUGUCAUUAGCUAUUAUCUUUGUAUUCAGGAAACAUUAAAAAAGAAAAAUGGCAUUUGAGAUGGGUGUUGAAAGAUAAUGAUGGAGAAUUUUGACAGGUGGAGGUAGAAUGAGAAAAGGCAUUACCAACGAAGGCCCAACUUAAUAAGAGCUAUUUUGCCUAUACUAAUGGACAGUUAACAGUCUGAUUUGGUGUAUUGCUUGGAAAUGAUCUUGCUCGCAAACUUAUUAGCUGUUCAAUUUAGUUUUAAGUAAAUGGGCAAGUGGCAAAUAUAUGAGGAAGUCAGAAGAACCUUUCUUAUAUUAACUUGAUGAGUCGCUAUACCAUUGAAAUCUCUUACCUCACCCAGAGCAGCCCCUCUGGAAGUGCUCUUUCAUACUUCAUGUCUCUUCUGGGUGUGUGAGGCAAACAUGAAGUUUAUAUCAGACACAUAUGAAUAUACUCAAUGAAUUUCUGCCUAUGGACAACUACCCUUUUGCAAUACUUACUUGAAGCAUGUUUUCUACAUGAAUAAUAUCUUGAAGCCCAAAUUAUAUAAUUGUAUCUGUAAUUUAUCUGCUUGAUAUACCCUUCACAAUAAUUCUAUAGCAUAUAAUUUUUCUCAUUUUUAAAUAUUUAUGAAGAAGCUUAUGUUGCAAGAGCUUCAUUCUCACUGUAUAUACCUGAAUGCUGUGAUAGGUUAGUAAUGGGCACUGAAUCAGAACUAUUUAUUUCUGUCCUACACCAAAGCCCUUGUUUUAUAAACUAGGCAACUUUACUCCCAGCAUGAGCAUGAGCAUGAGCAAAUGUUACGGCAAUAGGAAAGCAUAGUAUCAUUCAAAGAAUUAUCUAGAAAGUGGAUAAUUUUGGCCAAAUCUGAGAUUCUCAGUGCUGUUUAUACAUCACAAUCACCCAUGGGAGGUUUUAAAACUUAGGCUCAGACAUCAUCACAAAUCUCCACCACAGACAAAUUCAACCCCAAUUGCUGAGAGAGGGGUCCUGGCAUCAGAAGUUUUUAAGCUCCUGAGUGAUUCCAAUGUGCAGCCAGUACUGAGAACCACUGGACUAAAAUGAAGGGCACAUGUAUGGGGGCGGCAUGAAGAGUGAAUAGGGUUUAAAAAGGAAUAUUAGAAUCACAUGGGCAGGAUAAAACCCAAACAGCCUCACUCAGUAACUAUGUGAUCUUGGGCUAGUUACUAAACUUCUUGAAAUCUCUAUUUUCCUGUAAGAUGGGGAUAAACUAAAGCAUGUAAAAUACUUAGUAUUUGGAGUCAGUUUAAUUAAUGGUCAUUCUUACUAUUUAAAAAAAAUAAAUUUGAAAAAUGAUAAUAGGACUAUGUUGUGGAAAUAUUUGACUACCAACUGCAGGAAAGGAUAUUACUACGACAGCAUAGGUGACAAAAACAAAUUAGAGAUAUAUUUUUUGCUCAGAUGCUUAAAAUAUUUUUUUUCUUUUCAUAUCUUGUUUGCAGUUAAGUAAUCUUUGGUAUUAAGCAGUUUUAAUUGCAAUAAGCUUAUAAAUUAUUAGUACUCCAUAAUGAAGAGAAAUGAUAAAAGUCUGUCUUGUUUUGAUAAUAUAUGAAUAAUAGUGAGAAUUAUAAUGUGCUUUCUUUUACUAAGCAUCAGAUAUUUUUCAGAUGAAUAGAAUUUCGAUGAGUUAACUACCAAUUGCGUAGUACCAUUUACAAUCUCAUUUUUGAAAGACACUGUCUUGAAACAAUCUAGAACUGACAAAUGACAACAUAAGAUACUCUGCUUUGCAUAUUAAAGACUUUCACAUUCACUUCUCAUUUGGUUCUGCCCACAGCCCUGAGACAUGGGAAUUAAUGAGUUUUAUAAAGUUUAUUGGUUUUUAGGGGAGAGGGCUAUGACAAGAAUCCUUCCCUUCUAACUUUGAAUGUAAUGCUUCUUUUAUGACACACAUACUUAUUUGGAAUAUGUUGAAAGUCUAGAAACUAAGAAUUAAUAUGUAGGCAAAAGGACCAGUGCAAUGCUGUGAACUCGAUGUGAGUAGAUCUUAGGGAUUCUAAAGGGCACUCUAAUGCCUUUAGAUUUAAGCUGAAAGUCAGAGAAACAGUUAAGAUAGCAGAAACCUAAAAAUUCUCAAAAUAUCAAACAGGCAGAGUUAACUCUACCAAAGUCAGAAUGACUCAAAACACUGUUAGCAGCAAAUGAAAACAAAGAAAGAAAACAGCACUAUGCAACCUCUGGUUUGCUUAUGGUACUUACUAGAAGUGAGUAGUCUUGGCUGCAAUGAACUUUAUAGAAAGUGUUUAGCUUAGAGAAUGUCAGAAUCCUAUAAAUACCCUGGAAAUAGCGGGUGGCAUAAUGUCUUCUGCAGUCUCGUUUCAGCAGAUAAACUUCUUCAGUUCUAUUUAGAAUGCAUUUUUUGUACUACGGUUGAUAUUUCAGGCAACAGUGAUGUAUAUACAAGUAUCUUCAACAUUCUAUUAAUUUCAGGUUCAAUUUUUACUGAAAUCAAUAUCUAUUAAAAUUAUCAUGUUAUAAUUAAUAAUCUUAAAUUGUACAAAAUUCCUAUUCUCUUGUAUCUGUAUAAUAUCAAAUUAGAUGUCUAAAAAUCUAAUCUGAUUUUCAAAUUAACAAAAUAACCUAGAAGCAAUACUAUAAUCAUCUUCUCUAAUAUAUAUACUUAAGAUAAAACAGCUAAUUAUAAACAACUUAUACAUGGAAGUAUGCAUAAAUAUUGUGAUUUUUACUUAACACAGUGAUAAAGAAAUUGAUACAUUUAAAUAACCAUAUAUAUAGCCAAUUUGAAAUUUAGGUAUACUCCAAAAGUAGAUAUUUUGAAUUGAUAUGUUUAACUGGCUUAAUUCAACAUAAUUUAGGCCAGAUAUUUCAUAAAAUUGUGUUUAUUUCUAAAGUAAUGAGUGCUUCUUGUAAAUAAUUCCAAUACAAAAAUAUGUGGAGCAAAAUGCGACAUUAAGAAGCACACCAAAAUUAGGAUGGUCAGCGCCUCUGGCAAUGAGGGAAUGGGAUUAGAAGAGAGAACAAAAUGGUUGACAACCUUAUCUGUCAUGCUUAAUUUAUUUCAUAGAUAAAGUUAAAAUGAUGAAAUGUUUCUAUUGAUAAUCAUGGAUUCUAUGUAAGAAUUUGUUACAGUAUUUUUGUAGCUGUUUGUUUUUUUUAAGUUUCUCAAAAGUGUUUAAGAUUUAAAUUUGACCAUAUUACUAGGUAAUUGAUCUUGAUUUCAGUUAAUACCCUGGAGUUACAUAAACAGAAAUUUAAAAUAAUAUUUUUGAUUCUACAAGCAUUCCACAUUCAUUAAUGUAAUACAAGAAAACCAGAUCAUUCUACUGUGAUCAACUUACAAAUUGUGUUGGAAUCUGCCUGCAUAUAGCCCACCCCCUCAAUAAGGCACCAUAAAAGCUAUUUUAAGUAAUAUUCUCUCAAUCAUAAUAAAACACACAUAGCAAGACCAAAAGGCAGUGAUUCCUUUUUCCAUUUCCAACUUGUCCUCAAGCUAAGCAGUCCGGCAACUCAAGCAAAAACUGUGUUUCAUAAUAUGAACAGCCACUUAAAUACUUUCUCCCCAUCUCUUUAUGUUUCACUGCUGGGGAAGUUAAUAAUGAUUAAAGUAGGAAGAUUUUUUGUUUUAAAUCAGAAAGUCAGUUGAAAGAAACCUAAAGUUCUGCCAUAAAUAUCUAGCAGGUGCUGAUGGCCACCUGCCACACUUGCACCAGAUUGUCUAUGUAGCCAGCAGUCUGGCCAUCAGCAGACCAGAGAGGUGCAAUGGGGAGUCUCUGCCUUGCUGCAGAUUCCGAUAACUUCUUGCUUAAUUUCUAUGGUGGUCUUGCCUUCUAAGUCCCAGAUCUUGAUGCUGAGGCCUGUGGUAGCGCAGAACCAGUAGCAGUUGAGGCUAAAGCACAGGGCAUUGAUGAUAUUCCCACCACAUAGCAUAUCAAGGUGCUUGCCUUUGUUGAGAUCGCAUGGCAUGGCAUGGCAUGGCCAGCAUUGCCUCCAGAAGCACAGAGGGAUCCAUCUGGAGAGACAGUCACAGUGUUCAGAUGGACUGUGUGGCCAAAGUGGUUCAUCUUCAGCUUGCAGUUAGCCAGAUUCCGUACCUUGACCAGCUUGUCCCAGCUACAGAGGUGAUAGUGUUGCUGCCGUUAGGUGAGAAGUGGACAUAAGACACCUACUCUGAGUGGCUCUCCACCUGGACAGUGUAUUUGUAUAUACUCAGGGUUAUAACCAUAACUAGACGGUUUUAUCUCAGGAUCUAGAGACAAUCUACAGGUUGUCAAUGGAGAAGGCCACACUCAACACGUCCUUGGUAUGGCCUACAGAUCAUCUCAUAGUGGUGCCCUUUGUCAGAUCCCAGAAGCACAGGUUUCCAUCUCAGGAGGCUGAGAGGAAAAAGUGGCCACCUGAAGAGAUGAUUUUGUCAUAGACAAAGUGGAAAUGACCCUCCAGGGCAUGCUGUGGGAUGCCAUAGUUGGUUUCGUCCCUGUUCAAUGUCCACAUGAUGAUGAUUUUGUCUCAAGAGGUGGACUGUAUCAUGUCCAGGGCAGUAGCGAUCUGGUUACUCAGGUAUUGUGGCCUUCAAGAGUGUCACAAAGGGUCUUCUGCUCUGUCAUGGUGGUGGUGAGGUCAGGUGUCACUGCAGCAACGAGGAUGCCACUCAGAGAGACCAGAGGGACAAACACCACAGCCAGUCCUGCCACAGCCCUGCCACAAAAAACCUGUGAACUUAUGAAUCAAGGCAUCUUGGCCCUGGUCAGCUCCAUUGGCUGCACGUCAGCAGGAUCCCUCCAGUCUUUGGCAGACGCCAUGCAUAUCCCCCACCUCUUCAUUCAGCGCUCAACAGCUGGGACCCCAAGGAGUGGCUGUGGACUCACCCGGAGCAACAGGAAUGAUGACUACACUCUCUCAGUUCGCCCACCUGUCUACUUGCAUGAUGUUAUCCUAAGAGUGGUCACAGAGUAUGCCUGGCAGAAAUUCAUUAUAUUCUAUGAUAGUGAAUACGAUAUCCGUGGAAUACAGGAGUUCUUGGACAAAGUCUCUCAGCAGGGAAUGGAUGUUGCACUUCAGAAGGUAGAAAACAACAUCAAUAAAAUGAUUACCACUCUCUUUGACACCAUGAGAAUAGAAGAACUGAAUCGCUAUCGAGACACUCUUAGGCGAGCGAUCCUUGUUAUGAAUCCUGCUACAGCCAAAUCCUUCAUUACUGAGGUUGUGGAGACUAAUUUGGUUGCUUUUGACUGUCACUGGAUCAUUAUAAAUGAGGAAAUAAACGAUGUGGACGUACAGGAACUUGUAAGAAGGUCAAUUGGAAGGUUAACGAUUAUUCGGCAGACAUUUCCAGUUCCCCAGAACAUAAGUCAGCGGUGUUUCCGUGGCAACCAUCGAAUAUCUUCAACAUUGUGUGAUCCAAAGGAUCCAUUUGCUCAGAAUAUGGAGAUUUCCAACCUUUACAUAUAUGACACGGUGCUUCUGCUUGCUAAUGCUUUUCAUAAGAAGCUGGAGGACCGAAAGUGGCACAGCAUGGCAAGUCUGUCAUGUAUCAGAAAGAACUCAAAGCCCUGGCAGGGUGGGCGCUCCAUGUUGGAGACCAUCAAGAAGGGUGGAGUUAGUGGGUUGACUGGAGAGCUAGAAUUUGGAGAAAAUGGAGGCAAUCCCAAUGUCCACUUUGAAAUCCUUGGAACCAACUAUGGAGAAGAGCUUGGCAGAGGUGUUCGAAAAAAUGAAAGAAUCAGACCACAGGGCUCUACUGGGAAAAUCUGGCCCCAGCUUGGUUGCUGGAAUCCUGUCACAGGUCUGAAUGGGUCACUGACUGACAAGAAAUUGGAGAAUAACAUGCGUGGAGUGGUUCUACGUGUAGUAACUGUUCUGGAAGAACCUUUUGUGAUGGUCUCUGAAAAUGUCUUGGGUAAGCCGAAGAAAUACCAGGGCUUCUCCAUUGAUGUUUUGGAUGCCUUAUCUAACUACCUGGGUUUUAACUACGAAAUUUACGUAGCACCGGAUCACAAAUACGGAAGCCCACAAGAAGAUGGGACAUGGAAUGGCUUGGUAGGAGAACUUGUCUUUAAGAGAGCCGACAUAGGGAUUUCUGCUUUAACCAUCACUCCAGAUCGUGAAAAUGUGGUGGACUUUACGACACGUUACAUGGACUACUCAGUGGGGGUACUACUUCGAAGGGCUGAAAAGACAGUGGAUAUGUUUGCCUGUCUUGCACCAUUUGAUCUCUCUCUAUGGGCUUGCAUUGCUGGCACAGUCCUUCUGGUGGGUCUACUGGUCUACCUCUUGAACUGGCUUAAUCCCCCACGAUUACAAAUGGGAUCAAUGACGUCUACUACUCUCUACAACUCCAUGUGGUUUGUGUAUGGAUCUUUUGUACAACAAGGCGGGGAAGUCCCGUACACGACUCUGGCUACCCGAAUGAUGAUGGGGGCUUGGUGGCUAUUUGCUUUGAUUGUUAUCUCAUCUUACACGGCAAACCUCGCUGCUUUCCUCACUAUUACACGCAUUGAAAGUUCCAUCCAGUCUCUCCAGGACCUUUCCAAGCAAACAGAAAUCCCUUAUGGCACAGUCCUAGACUCUGCGGUAUAUGAGCAUGUCCGCAUGAAAGGACUGAAUCCUUUUGAGAGGGACAGCAUGUAUUCCCAAAUGUGGCGGAUGAUCAACCGAAGCAAUGGAUCGGAGAACAAUGUUCUGGAGUCCCAGGCAGGCAUUCAAAAGGUAAAAUAUGGAAAUUAUGCUUUCGUAUGGGAUGCAGCUGUAUUGGAAUAUGUGGCUAUCAAUGACCCAGAUUGUUCCUUUUACACCAUUGGAAAUACUGUUGCUGAUCGGGGAUAUGGAAUUGCAUUACAACAUGGCAGUCCUUACCGAGAUGUUUUUUCACAAAGGAUCCUGGAGCUUCAGCAGAAUGGUGACAUGGACAUCCUGAAGCACAAAUGGUGGCCUAAGAAUGGCCAGUGUGACCUGUACUCGUCAGUGGACACAAAGCAGAAAGGAGGCGCCCUGGACAUAAAGAGCUUUGCAGGGGUCUUUUGUAUCCUGGCUGCUGGAAUUGUCCUCUCCUGCUUCAUAGCCAUGCUGGAGACGUGGUGGAACAAGAGGAAAGGCUCCCGGGUUCCAUCAAAAGAGGCUUCAUCCCUGCAGAAUGAAACUACAAUAUCUGAAAGAAGGAAUGCUUGGCCAUUAAGGCCAUGUUUGAAACUUGGCAGCAAUACCUGGAGAAGCCAGGCAUCCAGUCAUAGCCUGCACCAAUCAUCACAAAUGGGAGGACCCCUGGAUGACCCAUAACCUCUACCAGCACAAGAACUGCUGAUCUGUUUUCCACCUUAUUGAUUUCAGGACCCAUUAGAUCCUGUAUUCAAAACUGGUGAGCUAAUGUAUUAUCUCCUAAAUUAAAAACUCCUAUCCAGUUCAAGGAAGCUGACCUCACCAGAUUGUGACACACAGAAAUCCUUGCUGUAAUCCACUCAUAGAAGAGUAACGACAGGACUGCUGCUUUCAGCCACAGGUCAUGGAUCUUGCCUGCGCCAGCCCAUUAGCCUUAGAAGGAUGCUUCUAUGCAGUGGACUUCUUGCCUAGAUGUCCUGGUCAAGAGCACUCACACUGAGGUCCAAGUCUAUACCACAGUAGCUUUGUCCUCAGCUUCUAUCUGUGCACGAUUUUAAACUCUGGGUCUUAGGACUUCUCAUAGCCAGAGAUCUAGGGAGACAUGAAGGACCAAGGAGAAUGGCAGAACUUAACCAGAAAAAGACAGACGGCUCUUCUAAUGCUUAUUGAAUCACUGGUAACUGUGGUUAAACAUCUUUGGAGGUUUUAUCACAGAAUUCUCUCCAUAUUUCUAGAACAACAUUAUUUCAUACUUACCAAAAUUGGCUACUUUCCUCCACACCAAGGGACAUUACCUUUUUCCCCAAUGGCCAUCAAAUGUCUACAUUUUGCAUGGAUUCCUGGCUAAUGUAGAGCCUCCAGUUUGAAUCCACACUUAGUACAUGUGUCAUUGUAAACAAAGAUCACUUGGAUCUUAGGAUUACACCCUGGAAUUGCAGUGCCUGUAUAUACUACCCAGCGCUAAGAUAAGUUUGUUUUCCUUAUACCCACUUCCACAUUCAUUUAUAAUACCUCUUCAAUGCAAAAUGUAUUUUACAAGUAAAAUAGGGAAGCAUCAUAUGAAAUAUCCCAGCCCCUCAUGAACUCAAUCAGUUUUUAUUGAGGACCACUAUGUGCCAAGCACUGUAUUACAUUUUGGGAAUACAAUGAUGAAUGAGUCAGAAUCCUUUCCCUAAGAAGUUUGCAUUCCAGUGGGGAAUCCAGAUGAUUAAACAGCAUGAAGAGUGCUAGAACAGGCUAACAAUGGCCAUAAGUAUUCCCUCAUCUCUGUUCCUUAAGCACCCAGGGAGCUCCCAGUUGCCCAAGCUGAUGCACAGAUGAUCUAUUAUGCCAAAGCAACCUAAAAGAUUAAAGCCAACAAGCAGCAGUCCAGGAGGAGCCUCUACAAGUAGUGAUCCCAUGGGUUCUUUUACUAAUAUAUUAUUUCUAAAUAAUCUGACUUUCAAACAAGUUAGGUGUUCACUUACUGAGCACCUUCUUCAUUAUGUCAUCAAACUGAUAACCCUCAAGUUGUAGCUGCUCACAGGUGAAAAUCAGGCUAUAAAGUCAAAAGACAGAGCUUCAAGUUUGGGUCUUGGUGCUUACCAUGACUGUGGGCAAAUCACCUACUUUCUGGUCUUUGGUGUCAUUCUUUGCAAAAUAAAAGUAAAAACAUUAUAUACUGUACCUACCUCACAGGGUUGUUGUGAGAAUCAAGUGAAAAGUAUGUGAAAGAACUUUGUAAACUUUGUUAUUUUUAAUCACCCCAUUUCCAUGGGUUCUUCAUCUUCUCUACGUAAUACAAUACUAUAAUUCACCUGAAGGAUGUACUCUUACCCACUCUGUUCCUACCUCUCACCCUUACACAAGUGAAUUGUACAAAGAAGAUGAAGUACAUGCCUUCCUGGAUAUCUAGUUUCAGAUGGAAAUUCUGAUACCUCACAGAAUGACAAAGAAGUAGUCCGGAGGACCAAAACCGGGGCUCUACUGCCAUAGAGACAUUCCACCAUUAACAUACCACUGGACCUGGAUAUCAGCCAGCCCUCUUGAUGGACAGUUGUCCACAGAGAACCCAUUCUUGGCCCCAGAGAACUACUGCAGUGGUUCAGGGAAUCAUCUGGGUUCUUUCUGGCUGCCAGGGGAGUCACCAGCCAUUCCAGGAAAGCGCAUGCUUCCGAAAAUAAAGCAAGAAGAUUGGUUAAAGGAGACACUGACCCCAUUAAACAAAAUACAAGCCUUCCCUGACUGCCUGACCUGUGAUAAUUGGGCUGCCAAGGGAGAUACCUAGACACUUAUUUAAAGCAAGGAUUUGGUGACACAUUUCUUCAUUUAGCAGUUUAUCCCUGAUGCCAACCUGACUCUUACUUCUCUGAUUUUUGAUUUGUCGACUCCCUGUCUGUCUAACAGACCUAUGAUAAGAUGUGUUUCUGGCUUUAAAAUCCCAUAUGCUCCCCUUACAUACACACAAACACACAAACAUCCACACAAUGAGGAAUGCCAGCAUUUUUCCUAUCUAUCUUACCCACUUGACCAAGCUUAGCCUGGCCUUCCAUUUCUGAUUAUUUCAUAUGGAUUCUGAUUGGCUGAUCCAAUUUGAGUUCAGUCUCACUGGACCAGUCGUAAUGUAUUCCAGGCUGAAACUCUGACUCCCUUUCAGUCCUGUGUAGAAGCUUAGAGUGCCCAUGAAGCCACGAUACCGAUACCCAGCAAUCCUUUAAACAAAGGGAGGUCUUUCAACUUAGAAUACACAUGCUUAUCCAAAACUAAGGCCGUAUUAGCAUGUAUCUCCAGGAAUAACAUAAAGUUUCUAUAAAAGUUCUCCUGAGCGAAUAGAAUGGUGACUAUGUACAAAAGAUCUGAUAGAAUUGGCAUCCAAGAAACUUUGUAAUAAGGUCUUAAGCCUAAAAUAGAAAAUUUCAACUACAAUUCAUUCUUCAGCUUCCUAGAGCAAGGAAGGCAGAUCACAGGGAAAAAUCGAUUCAUUGUUUAUAUCAGUUUCCAAAAUAUUUUCAAAUGGAAUGGAAAAUAAUUCACAAUUUCCUUCUUGCUAUAAGUCAGAAUGGCUGACUUCACACACCAAUUCAGUGAACUAAGAAAUUCCAAGACUUUUUCCUAUGGCUAUAAUAUUAAAAGUUAAUUUUAAUACCUAAAAAACAUUAGCAAUUAAAAACAGUGUCUUAUAUUGUAGUUUACAACCACCACUUGCUGUGGGAAGGGAGCCAGAGAGACUCAGAGUACCCGCCACCCAAGGUCAAAGGCACUGAGCCAAAGGAUCCAGCAAAGAGCAGGCCCAAGCCAGGAAGAAAAGCUGUUGCUGAAAUGUCAGACCAAGCAUAUGAAACAAGAUGAUCUCCAGGUCAUGGUAGCUGAGAAAGGAGAAUAGACAGAUCCAAGCUGGGAACCAAAUUAAGAUGUUGGAACAGGUACCAGAGUGAAUAAGACUGGGCAGGGGAUGGAGUCACCUACGGCCACACGUUUGUCGUACAGUAGCCUUUCUUGUAAGUUGCGAUACUACAUCCUAGUUUCUUUUUCAGAAAUAAAAUCCUUGGUAUUACUGAUGUAGCUUACAUAGCCAGCCCCAAGCAGAAAACUCUUCCUUUCCCACAGACAUACUUUUUACUAUCUUGGUUGAUAUAAUUUUCUUUUUCAGAGAUUUUUAAUUUUUUUCAUGAAUCUUUGAUAGAUUAUUUUAUCAAUAAAAAUUUUGUCAAUAAAUAAUUUUCCUGAUUGAACUCCAAGUCCUUCUUUGGUGAUUAAAGUUGGUAAUAAAAACAAAUUACUUUAA